ACAGCGCGUCGCGGCAGCCCCCAAGGAAGACCAGCCUGCCUCUGGUCGGUUCCUGGCGCUCUGCGUUUCGUGACCUUGUCCAGUAGAAGGCUAUUUAAUUUUCACAACUGCUUGAAUUUUGACAUACAAGAUGAAGCAAGAUGCCUCAAGAAAUGCUGCCUACACUGUGGAUUGUGAAGAUUAUGUGCAUGUGGUAGAAUUUAAUCCCUUUGAGAAUGGGGAUUCAGGAAACCUAAUUGCAUAUGGUGGCAAUAAUUAUGUGGUCAUUGGCACGUGUACGUUUCAGGAAGAAGAAGCAGACGUUGAAGGCAUUCAGUAUAAAACACUUCGAACAUUUCACCAUGGAGUCAGGGUUGAUGGCAUAGCUUGGAGCCCAGAGACUAGACUUGAUUCAUUGCCUCCAGUAAUCAAAUUUUGUACUUCAGCUGCUGAUAUGAAAAUUAGAUUAUUUACUUCAGAUCUUCAGGAUAAAAAUGAAUAUAAGGUUUUAGAGGGCCAUACCGAUUUCAUUAAUGGUUUGGUGUUUGAUCCCAAAGAAGGCCAAGAAAUUGCAAGUGUGAGUGACGAUCACACCUGCAGGAUUUGGAACUUGGAAGGAGUGCAAACAGCUCAUUUUGUUCUUCAUUCUCCUGGCAUGAGUGUGUGCUGGCAUCCUGAGGAGACUUUUAAGCUAAUGGUUGCAGAGAAGAAUGGAACAAUCCGGUUUUAUGAUCUUUUGGCCCAACAGGCUAUUUUAUCUCUUGAAUCAGAACAAGUGCCAUUAAUGUCAGCACACUGGUGCUUAAAAAACACCUUCAAAGUUGGAGCCGUUGCAGGAAAUGAUUGGUUAAUUUGGGAUAUUACUCGGUCCAGUUAUCCUCAAAAUAAGAGACCUGUUCACAUGGAUCGAGCCUGCUUAUUCAGGUGGUCCACAAUUAGUGAAAAUCUGUUUGCAACCACUGGUUAUCCUGGCAAAAUGGCAAGCCAGUUUCAAAUUCAUCAUUUAGGACACCCUCAGCCCAUCCUCAUGGGUUCUGUAGCCGUUGGAUCUGGACUGUCCUGGCAUCGAACUCUCCCUCUGUGUGUAAUUGGAGGAGACCACAAGCUGUUGUUUUGGGUGACUGAAGUAUAAAGUGUUUUCUGUACCUUAGAUUCACAAACUUUGUAUUUUUAGUACAUAUUUUGAAGAAUUUCUAUAGUACAUAUUUUGAAGAAUUUUUAUAUCAAAUAUACCGUAUACUUUAGAAAAUGUCUCAGUUGCUUUUAUUAAAUAAAAUGUUGAUGGUUUGAAAAAUUAUUUUUCUACUCUGUUCUCUGUGUGUGUAUAUAUAUAUAUUUUUAAUCUUACAAAAUCAUAUUGACUCAGCAGCUCACCUCCAGAGAAGAGAUGACUAAGGAAAAAUAAUGCUUUUGAGUUUAUCAAAAAAGGAGUAUUUGAAGUGUAUCCUGUUUUCUAUACUUUGAGUAUAUGCUGUUUUUCUAAUUCUCAGGGACACAUUUAUCAAAAGAGAAAAAAAGGCCAGGUACAAUGGCUCACACUUGUAAUCCCAACACUUUGGGAGGCUGAAGGGAGUGGAUCACUUGAGGUGAGGAGUUCAAGACCAACCUGGCCAACAUGGUGAAACCCUAUCUCUACUAAAAAAAUAAAAAUAAAAAAAAUUAGCCAAGCAUGGUUUGGAAGACUGAGGCAGGAGAAUCACUUGAACCUGGAAGGCAGAGGUUACAGUGAGCCAAGAUCGUGCCACUUCACUGCAGCCUGGGCGACAGAGCGAGACUAUCUCAAAAGAAAAAAAAUCCAAGGAGAAAAAAAUAUCUUAGGGUAUUCUGGAAGUGGUUGUUGAGUAUAUAUAUGUGUAUGUGUACUCAAUUUAAUGUAAAAAAUUGUUUUCAGUUUCUUAAAUAUGUGAUUGAUUAUAUUGCUCAACCCUGUUUAUUAUACGCAGAUUCCUUUGGACGAGGUGUUCUAACAGUCUUAGAACAUCUGAUAUAUGGGAUCAAAAGUUACCUUGAAAAAUGACUUCUAGUGUAUACCUUUAACAGCCUCCUUUUUGUGAAUUUUCACUGUUCUUACCAAGAAACUUAAGUGUUUUUGAGAUGGGACCUGUUGGCAAUGGAACUGUGUUCACCCUCUCAAAGAUCAUUAAAAUCAACGUUAUCUAAGACAGCUGUAUCACAUUUUUGGGAUACAUCAUGGUACAGUCAGAAGCAUAUAAAAUUAUGGUUCUGCUUGUCAGUCACAUACAGAAUCCAAUACAUUUUGACAAACUGCCCAUUCCUGCAAGUUAAUGCCCUUUUUGAAGCUUCAUUUCCUCUUGUAAAGUACAGAUAGGAAUCAUUAUUUUGUGGAGUUGCUGUAAAGAUUAAAUAAAGGUGAAUGAAAAUA